GUACAGCGGCCUCCGCCGCACCGGGACAGCAGCCGCCGCCGCUGCCGCCGUCCUCCCCUGUCUACCCGGAGCUGUCUCGAGCUGAGCCCCCUACCGGGCCGGAUCCCGAGUAUUUUUUUUCCCAUUGUUUUUAAAUUUUAGAUAAAGCCUAGCCAUGGCUGCUGUUUAUUCUGGCAUUUCCCUUAAGCUUAAAAGCAAGACAACUUCCUGGGAAGAUAAACUAAAACUAGCUCACUUUGCUUGGAUUUCUCACCAGUGCUUUCUUCCAAAUAAAGAACAAGUGUUACUUGAUUGGGCAAGACAAUCAUUGGUUGCAUUUUAUAAGAAAAAGCUUGAACUGAAGGAAGAUAUUGUUGAAAGGCUUUGGAUCUAUAUAGAUAACAUUUUACAUAGCAGAAAAUUGCAGAAUCUCCUCAAGAAUGGAAAGACCAUUAAUCUUCAGAUUUCCCUAGUCAAGAUCAUCAAUGAGAGAGUAGCUGAGUUCUCUCUUUCGGGAUCCCAAAGAAACAUCUGUGCUGUCCUUCGAUGUUGCCAGGGCAUCCUGUCGACACCUGCCCUGGCUGUCAUCUACACGGCCAAACAGGAGCUGAUGGUGGCCUUGCUGAGCCAGCUUUGCUGGUCGGCCUGCAGGCAGCCCGAAGGAGCUGUGGUAGCCCAGUUGUUUGAGGUCAUUCACCUGGCCCUUGGCCAUUAUCUCUUGAUCCUGCAGCAGCAGGUCAACCCAAGACGUGCCUUUGGGGAUGUGACUGCUCACCUGCUCCAGCCGUGCCUGGUCCUGAGGCACUUACUCUCUGGGGGCACAUGGACGCAGGCUGGCCAGGGCCAGCUGAGGCAGGUGCUGAGCCGGGACAUCAGGAGUCAGAUUGAGGCCAUGUUCCGAGGAGGGAUUUUUCAGCCUGAGCUACUGUCAUCCUACAAGGAGGGGCUCUUGGACCAGCAGCAAGGGGAUGUGAAGACGGGAGCCAUGAAGAACCUUCUGGCUCCCAUGGACACCGUGCUUAACAGGCUGGUUGAUGCUGGCUACUGUGCAGCAUCCCUUCAUACCUCUGUUGUGGCCAACUCAGUGGCCUUGCUGUAUAAGCUCUUUCUAGAUUCUUACUUUAAGGAGGGAAACCAGCUUCUCUGCUUCCAGGUUCUCCCCAGGUUGUUUGGCUGCUUGAAGAUUUCACACCUGCAGGAGGAGCAGAGCAAAGCCCUGUCCACAUCAGAUUGGACCACAGAGCUUUUGGUUGUGGAACAGCUACUAAACUCAGUGGCCAACAACAAUAUCUACAACAUCGCUGCCGACAGAAUUCGGCACGAAGAGGCUCAGUUCCGCUUUUACCGCCACGUGGCUGAGCUGCUGAUAAACCAUGCACAAGCACCCAUACCGGCCUGGUUCCGCUGUCUGAAGACUUUGAUAUCUCUGAAUCAUUUGAUUUUGGAGCCAGACCUGGAUGACCUGCUGGCUUCAGCGUGGAUCGAUGCCGAGGUAACAGAGUUUCGAACCAAAAAAGCCCAGGAGGCGCUUAUUCGUACUGUCUUCCAGACUUAUGCCAAACUCCGACAAGUGCCACGGUUGUUUGAAGAGGUUUUGGGGGUGAUCUGUCGUCCAGCUGCUGAGGCACUGAGGCAGCCUGUGCUGGCCUCGGGCCCCUCCACGGUACUCUCUGCAUGCCUCCUGGAGCUGCCUCCAAGUCAGAUCCUGGACACGUGGUCCCUUGUGCUGGAGAAGUUCCAGUCUUUAGUCUUGCCCUAUUUGCAGAGUGAUGCCGACAUGGCCCUGAAAUCACUGUCACUGAGCUUGCUGCUGCACUGCAUCAUGUUCAACAUGAGGAGCCUGGACAGCAGCACGCCUCUGCCCAUUGUCAGACGGACACAGUGCAUGAUGGAGAGGAUGAUGAGGGAGCUCGUGCAGCCCCUGCUGGCCCUUCUCCCGGACACCCCAGGCCCAGAGCCAGAGCUGUGGCUGCAGAAGGUCAGUGACUCUGUGCUCCUGCUCUCUUACACUUGGGCCCAGGUGGACGCUAUGUUCAGUUUGAACUGUAGCCAGUAUCACUCUAUGUCUGGGCCCCUUAUAGGUGUUGCUCUGGAGAUCUCGAACCUCCCUUCGUUGCUCCCAGGUGUAAAAACACAGCAUUGGAAGAAGAUAGAGAAGUUUACAGCUCAGUUCAGCUCUCUUGGUACAUAUUGCUUAGAACAGCUGUACCUGCAGAAAAUGAAAAGGACUUUAAUGCAAACUAGUUUCCGGUCUGAAGGAGCCAUCCAAAGUUUGAGGUGCGAUGCUGCCUUUAUUAUUGGUUCCGGCAGAAAAAGCUUGAAUCAGAGAACGACGGCUUCCUGGGAUGGCCAAGUUGGGAUGGUGAGUGGACUCACAUACCCUGUAGCACACUGGCACUUGAUUGUGUCAAAUCUCACAAUUUUAAUAUCCUAUCUGUGUCCAGAUGAUGUGGGAUACCUGGCCAGUGUCCUGCUGAGAACUUUACCCAUGGGCAAAGCCCAGGAAGUCUCAAUAGAUGAAGAGGCAUACAUCACACUGGAAAAAAUAUCCAAAGCCUUCCUUCAUAGCCCUCUCUUUCCAGAGAUGCAGUCCCUUCAUUCUGCUUUCUUAACGUGCGUAACCACAAGUUGCUCCAGCAUUCUGUGUUCUGGUGCCCAGCGUGACUCAGGUCUUGUCAGUCAGCAGCUUCCCUGGCUUUUUGAAAAGGACCACAUGGUUGUGGGUCAUUGGGAAAACAGAUUUGCAAAAGCUGGACCCGAAGGUAUAGAACCUAGAGGAGAAAUUGCCCAGAACUUACUGUCCCUGGUCAAGAGUGACUUCCCUAUCCAGCUGGAGGGAGAGCAGUUGGAAAGCAUCCUGGGGCUUUUGGAAGUGAUUUCUGCCUUACAGCUGGACAGCCUCUUGCCACCCUAUCAUGUGCAUUAUUUUCUUGUGUUACUGUCCAUGGCCGUCACCAAACUAGGAUGCUCUUGCUCCUCCUCACUGGCUCUCAAGUUCUUGACGACUUGCUACCAACUUCUUGGUUACUUGCAAAAGGGGAAAAGUGCUCGCUCUGUGUUCAAGAUCAUGUAUGGUAGUGAUAUUUUUGAGGUUGUACUGACCUCAUUGUUCAGAGCUAGUAGUAGGUUCCUUAUUGAGAUGGAUGAUCCCGCUUGGCUGGAAUUCCUCCAAGUGAUAGGGACGUUCUUAGAGGAGCUAAUGCAGAUGCUCAUCCAAAUGAAGCUGAGCUUGGUGCUCAAUUUUAGAAAAAUCACCGCAUUCCUCUCUAGUUCCAAACCAUACACGGAGGCAGCUUCAAGCAAACAAUUAGAAAAUCAGAACCCCCAGGGCAGGCAGCUCCUUCUGGUGUCUUUAACCAGGUUGUGCCAUGUCCUGGGACCUUUCCUCAAAGAGCAGAAGCUGGGCCAAGAGGCCCCAGCAGCACUGUCUGAGCUGCUGCAGCAGGUUGUGCUGCAGACAGGAGCUGUGCUGCAGCUCUGCUCAGUGCCGGGGGCCCGGGGCUGGCGCCUUCCCUCGGUCCUCAUCUCAUCCGUCAGCACGCUCUUGGAAGCCGACCUGGGUCAGCACUGCAGGGAUGGAGGGGCCGACAUUUCCCAAGGAAGCGACAGGACGCUGCUCUCCCAUGUUGCCCUCUACCAGGGUGUUUACUCUCAGAUACUGUUGGAGUUGCCAGCUCUCGCGGGACAUGAUCAGUCUUUUCAGGCAGCCUUGCAGUUUUUGACUCUGUUCUUUUUGGCCCCAGAACUGCAUCCCAAAAAGGACUCCGUGUUUACCUCCAUGUUUCAUUCUGUGAGAAGAGUUCUUGCAGAUCCUGAAAUUCCUGUUCAGGUCACUCAGGAUAUUGAGCCUCAUUUGGGAGCCUUGUUCACCCAAAUGUUAGAGGUUGGGACGACAGAGGACUUGAGGCUGGUGAUGCAGUGUAUUCUCCAGGGACUGGAUGUCAGUAACAUGUGGAAAGCAGAUGUGCAGGCUGUUGUGUCAGCUGUUACACUGCUGAGGCUGCUACUGAACUGCCCACUCAGUGGAGAGAAAGCAAGUCUGUUGUGGCGUGCGUGUCCCCAGAUAGUCACAGCUUUAACACUCUUAAACCGAGAAGCUUCUCAGGAGCAGCCUGUGUCCCUCACAGUGGUCGGGCCUGUCUUAGAUGUCCUGGCUGCACUGCUGCGGCAGGGGGAGGAGGCCAUCGGCAACCCCCACCACGUCAGCCUGGCCUUCAGCAUCCUUCUCACUGUCCCUUUGGACCAUCUGAAGCCGCUGGAGUAUGGAAGCGUCUUCCCGAGGCUGCACAACGUGCUCUUCUCAAUCCUGCAGUGUCACCCUAAGGUAAUGCUGAAAGCCAUCCCUUCUUUCUUGAACUCUUUCAAUAGAUUGGUGUUUUCAGUUAUGCGGGAAGGGCGGCAGAAGGACAAAGGAAGCAUAGAUGACCUGCCUACGGUCCUAAAGUGUGCACGCCUGGUUGAAAGAAUGUACAGCCACAUCGCCGCACGAGCUGAGGAGUUUGCUGUGUUUUCCCCAUUUAUGGUGGCCCAGUACGUGUUGGAGGUACAGAAGGUGACCUUAUAUCCAGCUGUGAAAAGUCUGCUGCAGGAGGGCAUUUACCUCAUCCUGGACCUCUGCAUCGAGCCUGACGUCCAGUUCCUGCGGGCCUCGCUGCAGCCGGGAAUGAGAGACAUCUUUAAGGAGCUCUAUAAUGACUAUCUCAAGUACCACAAGGCCAAACAUGAAGGAGAGAAAAGAUAUACGGCCUAAGGCUAUGGGACAGAAGUGCCGCCAGUGACACUGUCCAGAGGCUUUGGCUGCAUGGUCUGAAAGAGCUGGAGAAUGAAAGACUUAAGAUGUUCUAAUUCGUAGUAUUGGUAUACAUAGAAAAUCCUUUGGGGUUUAUGUAGUAUAUUUUGAUGUAUUUUACAUCGUGUUUUUCUUACUAUUUUUUAAUACAUAGUUUUAUGCAGUAAGUAUUGCAAUAGAAUCCUGAAAAUUGACCCUGGGAUGAGAUUAAUUCAAUAGAAAAAUUGCUGACUCUUGGGACCUUUCUGUGUUUGGUUCUCGUCUUGGCUCAGUGGUUUGGUGUUCCCUCGUCUGCACUGGAAACUACAUAAAACUUGGCUUUUUACUUUGGGUACAUGGGCGUAUAAUUCAGCCCUGUUUAAAUAUACUUGCCUUUCAAAUUCUUCAAGUAACAUGGGAAGUAUUCUUGAAAUGUCACAUUUUCUGCCUUCCCUCUAAGUAUGCUUUCUGAAGAAGUCAGGGAAAGUUAGAGUCUGUGGCCUGAGGUGUCUGCUCUGGGUGGCGAUAGUGGGCACCUCAGGCAGGUCGGUGACGUUUAGCACAGGUGCCAGGGCUCCUGCCUGCUCCUCCUGUGUUAGCUCUGUGAAGUUCAUUUAGGAAUUUUUUUUUCCUAUGCAGUUUAAGAAAUAAUCCUAAUUGUUUUUUCUUAUUACCUAAGCAAUAUAUUUUUAUUAUAGCAACCUCAGAAAAGAAAAAUAAAAGGAUAAUUUAAAAAACUCAUUCAUAGUCUCAGUUACCCAGAUAACCUCGGUUGUCACCUUGGAGUAUCUUGUUGUAGUCCCUUUACUAUGUGUAUGUAUAUAGAUGUGCAUAUAAAUAUAUAUAGUAGCUAAAUUGGAUCAUAAAUGCAUUUUUUUAAAGUUA